AGUUUCAGACAAGCCUGCUUGCCGGAGCUCAGCAGACACCAGGCCUUCCGGGCAGGCCUGGCCCACCGUGGGCCUCAGAGCUGCUGCUGGGGCAUUCAGAACCGGCUCUCCAUUGGCAUUGGGACCAGAGACCCCGCAAGUGGCCUGUUUGCCUGGACAUCCACCUGUACGUCCCCAGGUUUCGGGAGGCCCAGGGGCGAUGCCAGACCCCGCGGCGCACCUGCCCUUCUUCUACGGCAGCAUCUCGCGUGCCGAGGCCGAGGAGCACCUGAAGCUGGCGGGCAUGGCGGACGGGCUCUUCCUGCUGCGCCAGUGCCUGCGCUCGCUGGGCGGCUAUGUGCUGUCGCUCGUGCACGAUGUGCGCUUCCACCACUUUCCCAUCGAGCGCCAGCUCAACGGCACCUACGCCAUUGCCGGCGGCAAAGCGCACUGUGGACCGGCAGAGCUCUGCGAGUUCUACUCGCGCGACCCCGACGGGCUGCCCUGCAACCUGCGCAAGCCGUGCAACCGGCCGUCGGGCCUCGAGCCGCAGCCGGGGGUCUUCGACUGCCUGCGAGACGCCAUGGUGCGUGACUACGUGCGCCAGACGUGGAAGCUGGAGGGCGAGGCCCUGGAGCAGGCCAUCAUCAGCCAGGCCCCGCAGGUGGAGAAGCUCAUUGCUACGACGGCCCACGAGCGGAUGCCCUGGUACCACAGCAGCCUGACGCGUGAGGAGGCCGAGCGCAAACUUUACUCUGGGGCGCAGACCGACGGCAAGUUCCUGCUGAGGCCGCGGAAGGAGCAGGGCACAUACGCCCUGUCCCUCAUCUAUGGGAAGACGGUGUACCACUACCUCAUCAGCCAAGACAAGGCGGGCAAGUACUGCAUUCCCGAGGGCACCAAGUUUGACACGCUCUGGCAGCUGGUGGAGUAUCUGAAGCUGAAGGCGGACGGGCUCAUCUACUGCCUGAAGGAGGCCUGCCCCAACAGCAGUGCCAGCAACGCCUCAGGGGCUGCUGCUCCCACACUCCCAGCCCACCCAUCCACGUUGACUCAUCCUCAGAGACGAAUCGACACCCUCAACUCAGAUGGAUACACCCCUGAGCCAGCACGCAUAACGUCCCCAGACAAACCGCGGCCGAUGCCCAUGGACACGAGCGUGUAUGAGAGCCCCUACAGCGACCCAGAGGAGCUCAAGGACAAGAAGCUCUUCCUGAAGCGCGAUAACCUCCUCAUAGCUGACAUUGAACUUGGCUGCGGCAACUUUGGCUCAGUGCGCCAGGGCGUGUACCGCAUGCGCAAGAAGCAGAUCGACGUGGCCAUCAAGGUGCUGAAGCAGGGCACGGAGAAGGCAGACACGGAAGAGAUGAUGCGCGAGGCGCAGAUCAUGCACCAGCUGGACAACCCCUACAUCGUGCGGCUCAUUGGCGUCUGCCAGGCCGAGGCCCUCAUGCUGGUCAUGGAGAUGGCUGGGGGCGGGCCGCUGCACAAGUUCCUGGUCGGCAAGAGGGAGGAGAUCCCUGUGAGCAAUGUGGCCGAGCUGCUGCACCAGGUGUCCAUGGGGAUGAAGUACCUGGAGGAGAAGAACUUUGUGCACCGUGACCUGGCGGCCCGCAACGUCCUGCUGGUUAACCGGCACUACGCCAAGAUCAGCGACUUUGGCCUCUCCAAAGCACUGGGUGCCGACGACAGCUACUACACUGCCCGCUCAGCAGGGAAGUGGCCGCUCAAGUGGUACGCACCCGAAUGCAUCAACUUCCGCAAGUUCUCCAGCCGCAGCGAUGUCUGGAGCUAUGGGGUCACCAUGUGGGAGGCCUUGUCCUACGGCCAGAAGCCCUACAAGAAGAUGAAAGGGCCGGAGGUCAUGGCCUUCAUCGAGCAGGGCAAGCGGAUGGAGUGCCCACCAGAGUGUCCACCCGAACUGUACGCACUCAUGAGUGACUGCUGGAUCUACAAGGUUUCCAGCGCCCACGCGGACUCCCCUCUGGGCCUCUGCAUUCACCGCUGCCGCUGCCUGGAAAGCUCUCCCCGUCCCCACCGGUGAUGUCCCCUAGGAAAGCUCCCCGUCCCCCGGGGUGAUGUCCCCUAGGAAAGCUCCCCGUCCCCUCCCGGGUGAUGUCCGCUAGGAAAGCUCCCCGUCCCCCCCAGGUGAUGUCCCCGAGGAAAGCUCCCCGUUCCCUCCCGGGUGAUGUCCGCUAGGAAAGCUCCCCGCCCAGGCUCCCUGGGUAUGGAGGAGAGGGGCUGAGGGACGCAGUUUCUGAUCACUGCUUGCACACCUCCUGUGAUGGGCAGCUCAUCCAUUACCUCUCAACGCAGCCUGGGCUGGUAAGUGAGUUACAAUUCUUAGAAAGGUUUUCCAGCUGCUGACACCAACCUUGACCCCCAUUCCCUUUACCGUUCCAAGACCAUACAGAGCACACCUCUUCUCCAAAUAUCUCACUCCUCCUCUAUUGAUCAUGUGCCUAUUCCAGACGUGUGUCAUGAGGCACACAGGCUCAGGGUGAUAACCACUGGCAUGGUGGCAGCCCACUGGGCCCUGGAGGUCCAGAGAAGCUCCUGAGCCAGCUGAGAGGGGCCAAUCUGGUGGGCUUCCUGUAGGAGGGAACGCCUUAGCUGAGUUCUGAAGGGUGAGUGACAUUUGGUUGGGGACCGUAAAGAAAGUAUCCCAGGGAGCAGGAAUAGUGUGUAGUGGGAGAGAAUGUCCUUCUGGAAACAAAGAGAGGUUUUGGCGGGGCUGGAAGGCUGAGUUUGGAAAUGGGAAGAAAACGCAAGGCCUGGUGCGGUGAUCAAGAUGGGAGGUCAGUAACAUCCUCUUUGUUUCAUAUUUCCUGACUCCUUGGCCAGGAAGCAACUAACAUCUCCAUCUACCAGGUCCACGGCUUCCUAGCAUUGGGUUUUACCAUUUUAAAAACAUUUUUUAAUUUUAGAUGGGAAAAAUAUCUUAUUGUGUAAAUUAAGACAAAUUAGCAUUUCUCUUGUAAGUGGCGAAGUUGAGCAGUGUUUUCAGAUGUGCGCCAGCUUGACAGAUGCCACCUCUUGCUGUGAACGUCUCAUGGCCUCAUGCCCAGCACAGAGCUCGCACCUUCUCAGGCCCCAUCCUCUGCUCUGAGCAAAAGGCCAAGGGCGUAGGCUGCCCUGUGGCCACAUGGGUGAGGAUAUGGUGAAUCAGUUUCCUGUUCUGCUUCCAUUCACCUUUUGUCCCUUCAGGGUUUCAAAUUUCUCUCUUCUCUGUUGGAGGCUGGGGUCCCAUGUGCCUGUAGCUUUGUCCUUGUCUGAGGUAUCUCUGAGCUCAAAUUAGAGGGCUGUGAAGCCCCAGGAAGGUAUUUGUGGGAGGCAAUUCUGAUGUGCUGGGUGCCUCGAACACACAACUUCCUGUUUAAUUCUCAAAACAUCUGCCUGGGGUGGGGACUCUUGAACCCAUUUUACAGUUGAGGAAACCAAGGCUCUGAGGACUUGGUUUACAGACCCAACAUGCCCACUAUCCCAAGGCCAAUAUGUAAGAGGCAACUCUAUUGGCAGCUUUUCUGGGCUUCAUUUAACAAACUCCUCUGUAGACAUUAAGGUUCUGUUUAAUUCAUGUUCUAGAGGACAGAGGUUGUUAGCUCUCCAUCUUGAGGCAAAACUCUUUGUCCCACCCUGCCCAAUCAAGGCAUGGAAGCCCUGUUUCUCAUCUAGGAAGGGGCUGUGGUGUUCAGCUCAGCACCAACCUUAUACUUCAGGGAGAGAAAUGGGAAAGAAAAAAAGGGAGAAGAAAGCACAUACAUUCAUCCUCCUCGGAACCAAACUCCUGAGUUAGGCCUUGGUUCUGGCUCCGUGGCUGCCACUAAAAUCCCAUGUGGCCUUGUUAAAUCCCUCCCACCUCUGGCUCUCCACUUCCGCUUCUGUGGAGUUUUUAUUCUAGCAAUGAAACUUUUCACAUAUGAGCUCCUGGUUCUUUCUUAUAUCUGCCUGCUUUUGUCUCAUAGUCUCCUGUUCUUUCUUUUCUUUGAGAUAAAGUUUUGCUCUUGUUGCCCAGGCUGGAGUGCAAUGGCGCGAUCUUGGCUCACUGCAAUCUCCACGUUCCGGGUUCAAGCGAUUCUCCUGCCUCAGCCUCCUGAGUAGCUGGGACUACAGGCACCCGCCACCAUGCCCAGCUAAUUUUUGUAUUUUUAGUAGAGAUAGGGUUUCACCAUAUUGGUCAGGCUGGUCUUGAACUCCUGAUCUCAGGUGAUCCACCCGCCUCGGCCUCCCAAAGUGUUGAGAUUACAGGCAUGAGCCACUGCACCCGGCCUCCUGUUCUUGUUUAUGGCUGUUAUUCCCUUCUUUAUCUCUUUGAGUUUUUAAUAUAUUUAUUGCAAAAUUCUUUUAAGGUUGCACUAUUAUUCUCUAUUUCCUCAGACGUAAAUUCUUCCAGUUGGGGAGUUUGUGGAAAUUUCAUGAAGUGGUUGUGAAUCCAUUGUCUCUUCAGAAUAUUUCUUGCAUGUGUAUCUUGUAAGGGCUGUAUAUGAGAGCCUGUGCUCUUGGCUUCAUACAUUAGGGGGCCCUGCAUUGGUACUAGCCUCCUAAUGGGUAGGUGGUGGGGGGCUUCAACCCUUGUCUCUGGGCAUCUCUGCAGUGGUCUCUUGUAUACCUGGUAUUUUCCUGUCAUUGCUAAGUGUUUGAAGAAUGGUUUCUAUGUGUACUUGGUCUGCCAUCUUGAAUGAAAGUCCAAUUUCACCAUCUGUAAACAUUUCACAGAUGAGGCACCGGAAGUUCAGGGAGGUGGCCUGACUUGCCCCAGUCCACACAGCUAGGAGGGAGAAUUUGAACCCAGCGAAACCCUAUCCACUCCCCGCUCCUCGGCAGGCCCUGGCCCGGUGCUCCCCUCAGCUCUGACUCAUUGCUAGCUCUGCAUUCCCUGGACACCUUCUUCCUCAGAGAGCUGGGAGAAUGGCCUCUACCCUGUAGACACGCUAAAUAAACUCAAAAUUUUGUUCUGGUGGA